GAUACAGUUCCGGUGGGAGAACGCGGCUGCGAGGUUUUCGGCUUUGGCUCCUGAUAUGCAGCGACAGAAUUUUCGGCCCCCAACUCCUCCUUACCCUGGUCCGGGUGGAGGAGGUUGGGGUAGCGGAAGCAGCUUCCGGGGAACCCCGGGCGGGGGCGGACCACGGCCGCCCUCCCCUCGAGACGGGUACGGGAGUCCGCACCACACGCCGCCGUACGGGCCCCGGUCUAGGCCGUACGGGAGCAGUCACUCUCCGCGACACGGCGGCAGCUUCCCGGGGGGCCGGUUCGGGUCUCCGUCCCCUGGCGGCUACCCUGGCUCCUACUCCAGGUCCCCCGCGGGGUCCCAGCAGCAAUUCGGCUACUCCCCAGGGCAGCAGCAGACCCACCCCCAGGGUUCUCCAAGGACAUCUACACCAUUUGGAUCAGGGCGUGUUAGAGAAAAAAGAAUGUCUAAUGAGUUGGAAAAUUAUUUCAAGCCUUCAAUGCUUGAAGAUCCUUGGGCUGGCCUAGAACCAGUAUCUGUAGUGGAUAUAAGCCAACAAUACAGCAAUACUCAAACAUUCACAGGCAAAAAAGGAAGAUACUUUUGUUAACAUUUCUGAAAUUCAACUGGAAGCUUCAUGUGUCAGGAACAUCUUGGACAAAACUUUAAGUUGUGUUGAUAUAAAUUUACCCAAAGAUGAUGACUUUGAUUGGAUAAUUAGUAAGGUCUUUUUGUUAUUUUUCAUCGUAUCAGGUAUUGUUGAUAUUAGAGAAAAAAGUAGGAUAACUUGCAACAUUUAGCUCUGGAAGUACCUACCACAUUUUAGAGAUUUACCGUUUCCAUAUAUUUAACAUUCCUGGUUACAUAAUGGACAUUUGUCUUUUAAUGUUUUUUCAAUGUUUUAAAAUAAAACAUUUUGUCUUCUAGCUAUUGUGGUUUUGUGGUAUGAUAAAGAAGUAGACUUACUACAGUAAUGCUUUGUAGUCACUUAGAGUUCAUAGGUAAAUGUUUUGCAAAUUAUUUUUGAAAAUGAAAUAGGUAAACCAUCCUUUGAGCUGUAGACAGCUCUGUAUUUGUUCGUAAAUAAUGAGGAUGAGAAUAACAGAGUUCUGUUCAUACUCAUUUUAUCUAAUGCUUCUGUUAAAAUGCAUUAAAACUUGAAGCCCCAGAAACCCAUUUAAGCAUAACUUUAUACUCAUUUAACUGGAAAAGGCAAGAAUAGACCAUGCAUUGCUAAAUCAAAGUGUUCUAUCUGAAUUUCUCUAUACCUCUUAGCAUUAUGGAGUUAGUUUCUCUUGAGGCCAAAGAAGAUAGCUACCAGCAGCCUCAAAUCACUUCCAUUGCAAAAAGAACAUCUCUCAUCUCCAUCAAUCCAAGAGAAGACAAAUUUGCCAUACUUAGAUCAUGUUUCUGUAUUAUUGAACCAAUUAACUGUGGCCAAGGCCACAGUGAGACCUAAUUAACUUGAAUCAUGGACACAUCACCAUAAUGAGACAGGAUUCUGUGACCUUGAACACCACUGGGCCUACCUGGAGUAGAGAAGUGGUUUUCCAAAUUAAGGGAUGCUAUGGAUAUAUACCUAUAGUUCUGGAGAGAAAAAUAUGGAAGAAUUGUUACCCCAACUAUUUUUUAAAAAUCAAGUGGUUUUUUGUUUGUUUUUUGAGAUGGAGUCUGUUGCCCAAGCUGGAGUGCAGUGGUGCAAUCUUGGCUCACUGCAACCUUCGGCUCCUGAGUAGCUGGGACUACAGGCACAUGUCACCAUGCCUGGCUAAUUUUUGUAUUUUUAGUAGAGACCAUGUUUUGUUUUUUUUGUUUGUUUUGUUUUGUUUUUGAAAUAGGGUCUCACUCUGUUGCCCACGCUGGAGUGCAGUGGCGCAAUCUUGGCUCACUGCAACGUCCGCCUCCCAGGUUCAUACGAGUCUCCCGCCUCGACCUCCUGAGUAGCUGGGAAUACAGGCACGCGCCUGGCUCAUUUUUGUAUUUUGAAUAGAGAUGGGGUUUCACCGUGUUGGCCAGGCUGGUCUCGAUUGAACUCCUGGUCUCAAGUGAUCCCCUACCUUGGCUUCCCAAAGUGCUGGGAUUUCAGGCAUGAGCCACCGUGCCCAGCCCAGAACAUGUAUUUUUAGUAUUUUUAGUAUUUUUAGUUUCACCAUGUUGACCAGGCUGGUCUCGAACUCAUGAUCUCAAAUGAUCCACCCAUCUCAGCCUCCCACAGUGCUGAGUUUACAGGCGUGAGCCACCAUGCCCGGCCAAAAUCAGGUGUUUUAACAUGUAACACAGACUCUAGGCAUUUUGAAGUUACAAAAUACGAAGAUAGAGCUAGUAAAACUUUUGUUUCAACAUUCCCAGAAAGAAACGUGUAAAAACAAAAUGGUCACACCUCCUAUUUGAACCAUACCCACAGAAAUUUGUUCAUUAGGUAUUUCACAGAGACUAGAAAAUAAGAAUGGAAGGCUUUUAGAUUAAUAAAAGCUCCAUGAAAGCCAGGAUUUUGGAAAUGCUGUUUCUACAAGUUACUAGCUGGAUGAGUUCACUUCUCUAUGCCUCAAUUUUCUCAUGUGUAAGAUGAGAAAAUUAAUAGUACCUGUGUCAUAGAGGUGUUGUGUUGGAGGAUUAAAUGAAUUUAUGUAUGAAACUCUUAAGCCAGAGCCUGGCACAUAGUAAGCACUCAAUAAGUGGUAGCUGUUACUUUCUCAUUUACCCCCAUUUCCUUAGUUUUUAGAAUAGUGUCUGCAAGAUAGUAGGUACUUAAGUGAUAAAUGGAUGUAGAAAUUCUGAUUGUAACUACUAUAUUGUUCUACCUACACCCUGUAUAUAAAAGGGAUAACUUAGUAAUUUUUCCCCAGUAUUUUAAAGAAAAAGUCCUUAUUCCCAACAUUAUGUCUUUCCAGAUAUGUUGAGGUCAUGAUGUAUAAUGGAAAUUAAAGCAAAGGGAAUACUUUUUUAAAUACUUUAUUGAACUUUAUAGGUAAGAAAUGUUGUCUUUAGGAAAUGACAUUUGGAGAUAAUUUACUGAAGCAUCUCUUAGAUCAUUGGGUUAUUAGUAAAGACGAAAACAGAAGUUAGGAUUUUGUGCCAGUGUAUUUAUAUCAUAUUUGGAAGACAUUCAAACUGUAACUCUUCUAAUGGUCUACGUACAUUUUAUUUCACUGUAAGUGUAACAUAAAACAAAGGUAAAAUUUCUUGCUAACGCUUACCAACAUCUACUUCUAGAGACCUGGCCUGAGUUUUUUAAGAAAAAUUUUUGUCCUCAGGAAAGAUGCAUACACUGUAAGUAGUGUAUUCAGUUAUCAAAAUUCUUGUGGCAUUGGCCAUUUGGUUUGUUACCGUUACUCUAUUUUUAUUUAUCUGAGUAAAAGGAAUUGAUUAUUCUUUAAAAUGAAAGGGAUUGUUUUUUAAUGUUCUAGGAUACACAUUUUACCUCUAUAAAAAUGCUGAAUAACUUUUUAGAAAAACUUACAAUUAAGUAUACAUCUUAAAAAUUCAUAUGCUUAAAGGAUGGAAGUGUAGUCUAUAGUAGAGUCUUCAAACAAGGGUCUACAUACUCCUGGGAAUAUUAAACUUUCUAAGGGAUAUGCAGGCAUAAAUAGCUUUAAGGGAAUGCAAAUUCAGAUCGCAGUGCCCAUGUAAAUCCUUUAUUAAAAUUGACCUACAUAAAAACAUAUCCAUAUCAAGGGAUCAUGCCAGUUCUUUUUCCCUGCUGCCUUUUGGUAAUCACUGGUCUCCCAUUUUACAAAAGAAACCUAUGGCAAGUUGUGUUUUGCAGAAAUGACCCCAACAAUAUUUAAAGUCUCAUACCCUUCUCGAACCUUGCCACUACCCUUAUCAAGAUGUGGAGUUACGUCCCUUCCCUUUGAACAUUAACAGACUUUUUUUUUUUUUCAAAGAGUUAGAGGGUCUCCUUAUAGGGGCCUCCCUGUAUUACCCAGGCUGGUCUCUAACUCUUAGGCUUAAGGGGUCCUCCAGCCUCGGCCUCCCAAAGUGCUGGAAUUACAGGUGUGAGCCACCACGCUUGGCCCCUUAGCCAACUUCUGACUGCCAUAAUUAAGAGAAUAUGAUGGAAGUUAAUCUAUUUUCAUUGUGGGUAAAGUGUGGUGUUAAAAAUGAGUUAUAGGCCAGGCACUAUGGCUCACACCUGUAAUCCCAGCACUUUGGGAGCCCAGGUGGGCAGAUCACUUGAGGUUCGGAGUUUGAGACCAGCCUGGCCAAUAUGGUAAAGCCUCGUCUCCACUAAAAACACAAAAAUAAGCUGGGCAUGGUGGCGCGCGCCUGUAAUACCAGCUACUGGGGAGGCUGAGGCAGAAGAAUCACUUGAACCCAGGAGGCAGAGGUUGCAGUGAGCCGAGAUAGUGCCACUGCACUCCAGCCUGGGUGACAGAGUGAUACUCCAUCUCAAAAAAAAAAAAAAAUAAGUUAUAUUGGCCCGUGUGGAGAUGUUCAGAAUUCAGAUGUAUUAUCAAGUUGGGAAAUAAUGAUGAAAGUGUUCAGUGACCUUGCCUUUUUGUUUCUGGACUAUUCAAAAAAUCAUUUCCUUUGUGGGUACAUUGUGUGAAAGGAAAGCAAAGAGCAUGAGUUUAACAUGAAGGAAAAGAUACCUUAUUUUUAGGCAAAAAGCAAAUGGUGAGGCUCUUUGCCUCAUCUACCUAAGAAUUAAAAUAUUCAAGAUUAGUAAAAAAGCAUGAUUAGUUUUGGUGAAUCUCCUGUGAAGCAAACUCUGUAUUUCCACCAUUCUUUUUUUUUUUUUUUUUUUUUUGAGACGAAGUCUUGUUCUGUCACCCAUGCUGGAGUGCAGUGGCACGAUCUCAGCUCACUACAACCUCUGCCUCCCAAGUUCAAGCAAUUCUCCUGCCUCAGCCUCCCGAGUAGUUGGGACUACAGGCAUGUGCCACCACACCCAGCUAAUUUUUUGUAUUUUUAGUAGAGGCAGGGUUUCACCCUGUUAGCCAGGAUGGUCUCAAUCUCCUGACCUCAUGAUCUGCCCAGCCUCAGCCUCCCAAAGUGCUGGGAUUACAGGCGUGAGCCACCGCGCCCGGCCCUCCACCAUUCUUGAUAAUUAUAAAGAGCCUGAUGAAGAUAUCUCAAUUCCUGUCUCAGUAGCAUAGUUUGCAUGAUAUCAAGGAGGAGGAAGUUAAAAGUUUCAUGUUUACUUCUGACAUACUAACAUUACAUCUUCAAGUUAAAAACAUUUUAGAAGUAAGUUCAUGAAUUUAUAUUUUCUGAAACAUUUUCAGAUUCUUAAGAGAAACAUUUUCAUUAACCCUUGCCAGUACAUUUAUUAUUAGGUUCUAUAAAUUCCAUAUUAAUUGUUUUACAUAGGCCAAAGUCUCCUGCUAUUGUCACUCAACCAUUUCUCUGUAUCAUUCAUUCCUACCAUAUACUUAGGUUUAAGUUAACAGAAAUAUGUUGUAGUUUUUACUGUAAAUAAGACACAUAAUCGCCUGGUUGGAAGGUAGUGAGUUAUCUUAAUUGAUUGUUCAGUCAGUUACAGAUCGAACUCUUUGUUCUCGUCUUCCCCCCGCUUCUCACUGCUGCACUUGACUAGUCUGAAAAAAAAAAAUACAUAGUAGUCAUCAGUACACCUGAUAUAAGCCCUGAACUUCCUAAUGACCUCUUUUUUUGUGUGUGUGUGACAGAGUCUUACUGUGUUGCCCAGGCUGGAGUGCAGUGGUGUGAUCUCGGCUCACUGCAACCUCCGCCUCCUGGGUUCAAGCAGUUCUCCUGCCUUAGCCUCCUGAGUAGAUGGGAUUACAGGUGCAAGCCACCAUGCCUGGCUAAUUUUUAUAUUUUUAGUAGAGAUGGAGUUUCGCCAUGUUGGCCAGGCUGGUUUUGAACAGCUGACCUCAGGUGAUCCACCCACCUCAGCCUCCCAAAGUGCUGGGCUUACAUGGGUGAGGCAGUGCACCCAGCCUGAAUUACCUCUUUUAUUUUGCUCAUAAUUUCCAUAAUUUAUCAUCUAAUUUAAGAUGCUUUGAGAUUCACUAUUAUUUUAUAUGCCACUUAGUAAAAAUACUGCCAGUUAAGCUGUGACAUGUCAUUGAUUAUAAGAUACAUCUUAAUUUCAGAGAUGUUAAAUACAUGUCUUAGUUUGAUAAAAUACCAUACAAUACUUUUCUUUUUUUUGAGACCGAUCCUGCUAUGUUGCCCAGGCUGGUCUCCAACUCCUGCCUCAGCCUCCCAAGUAGCUGGGAUUACAGGUGUGUGACACUACACCCAGCUCACAUACAAUACUGUUUUUUGUUUGUUUGUUUGUUUUUUGAGACAGAGUCUUGCCCUGUCGCCCAGGCUGCAGUGCAGUGGCGUGAUCUCGCCUCACUGCAACCUCCACCUCCCGGGUUCAAGCAAUUCUUCUGCCUCAGCCUCCCAAGUAACUGGGACAACAGGCACGCACCACCACACCCUGCUAAUUUUUUAUAUUUGGUAGAGAUGGGGUUUCACCAUAUUGGCAAGGCUGGUCUCGAACUCCUGACCUCGUGAUCUGCCCACCUCGGCCUCCCAAAGUGCUGAGAUUACAGGCCUAAGCCACCGUUCCUGGCCUAUAGUACUCUUAAAAGCAGAACAUAUACUUAGAUAUAAGUAGGUAUAUAGAAGUAAAUGUCUCCAAAAGGUAGUGUAGGACAAUACAUUUGAAAAUUGGCUUUAACCCAUCCUGGCUAACACAGUGAAACCCCGUCUCUACUAAAAAUAAAAAAAAAAAAAUAGCCAGGCAUGGUGGCGGGCGCCUGUAGUCCCAGCUAGUCGGGAGGCUGAGGCAGGAGAAUGGCAUGAACCCGGGAGGCAGAGGUUGCAGUGAGUUAAGAUGGCGCCACUGCACUCCAGCCUGGGCGACAGAGCGAGACUCUGUCUCAAAAUAAAAAAAAAAAAAAGAAAAUCGGCUUUAUUUAAUUAGGGUUAACUCUUCUCAGAUACUUGUAUUUGUUCAAAUUCAUUAAAAACCAUAAUUGAGGCUGGGCGCGGUGGCUCACGCCUGUAAUCCCAGCACUUUGGGAGGCCGAGGCGGGCAGAUCAUGAGGUCAGGAGUUCGAGACCAGCCUGCCCAACAUGGUGAAACCCCGUCUCUACUAAAAAUACAAAAAUUAGACAUGGUGGCAUGUGCCUGUAUCCCAGCUACUUGGGAGGCUGAGGCAGGAGAAUUGCUUGAGCCCAGGAAGUGAAGGUUGCAGUGAGCCAAGAUCUCACCACUGCACUCCAGCCUGGGCAACACAGGGAGAUCCUGUCUCAAAAAAGAAAAAAAUUUUUACAGUUGAAAGAUUGCCAACAAUCUAAAUGACCAUAGGAGAAAGGAUAAAUAAGUUGCAUAUUUGCACAGUAUAACAAGAUAGUUGAUUAAAUUAGAGCCAUUUGAUACAACAUGAAUAAAUCUAAAAUUGUGUACAAACAAAAGCCAAAGCAAAACUUAUGUGAUAUUCUUUACGUCAAAUUUAAAAGUCUGCAAAACAAUAUGCUGUACUCUCUAUAAAUGGUAAAUAUAAGGUCAUAGUGUAAAUACAAAUGAAGGUAACAUGCUUUAGAUAUAGUAAUUAUUUUGGGGUGGGUUCAGGGAGAUACAAGCUUCAGAUGGACAUGGAUGUGUGAGUGGAUAUGUAUUUCAAGUCAACCAAAUUUGGAAAAUGUUAAAAUUUAUUAAACCUCACCAUGGAAUACA